GACAGCCCACUGGAAAGCUUCAAUACAGCUGUGGAAAUCUGCACCCUAGAAGAUCCUAGUACAGAAAUUCUACAACCAACCAUAAUCAUGGAAGAGCCAACUUCCAGCACCAACGAGAAUAAAAUGAAGAGCCCCUGUGAAUCUAACAAAAGAAAAGUUGACAAGAAGAAGAAGAAUCUGCACAGAGCCUCAGCCCCUGAACAGAGUUUGAAAGAGACAGAAAAAGCAAAAUAUCCAACAUUAGUGUUUUACUGCAGGAAGAAUAAGAAAAGAAAUUCAAAUCAACUGGAGAAUAACCAGCCUACAGAGAGCUCCACUGAUCCAAUCAAAGAGAAAGGAGACCUAGACAUAUCUGCAGGAUCUCCACAGGAUGGAGAGGAAGAAAAGGAUUUGGUGUUCCUUGGAGCACGUGCAUGUUUAGAAGAGCACAUAAGAAGAUCUGUAUUGUAUGUAGGUGACAGUGACACUCUUUCCAAAAUGAAGACAUCAGAAUCACCACCUUCAGGCCACAUACCUCAGAGUGGUGUGUUUUGUAACUCACCCAAUGCUGUGAGCAACUGAAGGUCCUCAAAAGGAACAAGAACCUCACCCUACAGAAAUUUGCUUUCUCCAGUAUAUUGUAAACUCCAUGACAACAAUUAUCUCAGCCUGUUUUGU